GCCUUGAUUCCUGCAAAAAGAAAAAGCACAAACAAAACCAAAACAGAAUACUUGCAGGGGUUGCUCUCACGGGAAUAAGAGGUGGUUUCUGAAAUGGUUGGCGCCUAUUAAGCACCCAGUGAUCCAGUGGCAUGAACCCCAGGGGACAGCCGAGGGCGAGUGGUCUCGGAAGCGUGCCAUGUGCAGGACACAGCAGAGCUGGGAGUGUCAGCCGGGAGGGAAGCUGCUUGGAGGGAGGCUGAGAUGGCUCACUUCAGGUGUCUGAGGGAUGCCAUGUGGCAGAGAACUUGCACAUCCUUGAGGUGGUUCUGGACAGAGGACUCUCUGUGCUGGAGGCUGCAGUGUAAGGCAGAGCUGCCAAACAGCCAGCACCGCGUGACACAGGCUGACUGGGGACAUGGUGCAUUUUCCCCAUAGUCAAGAUCAAGCAGGGGUCAAAACACCUAGUGCUUUAGGGAUUUCAUACGGGGGAAGUGGGACUCCAAGGCCACUGAAACUGAGAUCCCGUGGUUCUUCAAGAACAAAAGACCUUUAAUUCAAAUACUUUACUAUUAAUAAUUGAUACCAUAUUUUCCCAUAUGAGUACAAAUGUACAUGGGUAUGUUCUACAGGAAGGAGGUUAUAGUUGUCUAAGAUGGUUUUAAAACUUUAUUCCUGUAAAUAUAGAACAUUUACAAGAGUGGGACAGUCUUGUGCUUUAUCUCACCUUUCUGAGAUGGGAGUUUUGGGGAUAACUUCCAAGAGACGUGUUGCUUCCUGUCCCUCAGAUGGGCCAGCCCAAGCCGGGAGGCUUCUUGGCCACAGGCAGCUCUCACCCAGGAUGUGCCACCAUGCUUCAUACCUCCUGAACGCUUGUAGCCAUGGGUGGAGCUCUGUGAUGUUUACAACAUGUAAGAAUGAAUCCCAACUGAUGAGGGAAUCUGGUUUCCAUCAUUGAUUGGAAACGGAUUCCUAUCCCUUUCCCUUGCUCUGGAUUUAAUCUUCCUGUGAGAAUGAUCUAAGCCACUUUCCUCUAUCAGAGGACAGAAGGGAAACCAGGAGAAAGGGAGGGAGCGACCGUUCCUAAUGAUCUCUGAGCCACCCAGUGCCCGCCGGCCCCGGUGGGGAGUCACGCACAGCACCUGUGUCCUUGCCUUCGUUGCACCCCUCCCUGUGUUAGAGAGCUGAGAUCCUGAUGUGAGUACCUCAUGUGGCCUCGUGUGUCCUCUGCUGAGUCUCACUGGGAAGCAGCACAAGAAAUGGAUGAGGCGGAGCAGACCUGGCCUUGGAAUCUGGCCCCGCGCUUAAGCGAGGAUGGUCUUCGUGGCCUUUCUGAGCUUGGCUUCCUCUGAGUGGCGGGAAGCCUCAUUGGUCAUUUUUCAGAGCCCCUUGGUCCACUCCUCGGCACUAAGACACUUGAGAAAGGCUCCUCUCUUCACUCAGCAUGCUAUGGGGUUACUUAAGUUUAUUUCUUAAUUGAAUUUUCUCAUUAAAACCUGCUUUCCCAGAUCUGUUUGGCAGCAGGACAGUUUCGAGGUGGUAGAAGAGAGGCCCAGCUUCCUCUGUAUUUCCUUUCCCUGACUUUCUGGAGGCAUUAUCGAAGUACGCUAAGCCGCACGUAGCUGAAGUGCACAACUGGAUGGCUUGUGUUUGUUUCAGUGAUAACACACAACAUCUGCCUCCCUGCUCUCCCCAGCCUCCCGUCUCUGAUCGCGCACUCCCUAGUUUUCCAGCCUCUUCUUAAGCAGCGAUUCCAGCUGGCAGCGCCGUGACAAGUGUUUCCGUAAGCAUUCCCACGAUCCUCUAAGUGAGGAGCAUGACCUCGGAACCAUGUGCCCGGUCCCCUCCCCUGACGUAGGAGGUAGUGGGAGAGUGAUCAGCAGCUGGACUGUGCCUUGGACCUAAUGAGGCGCCUGCCUCCCCAGCAAAUCGAGAAAAACCUCAGCGACCUGAUCGACCUGGUCCCCAGUCUAUGUGAGGAUCUCCUGUCUUCUGUUGACCAGCCACUGAAAAUUGCCAGAGACAAGGUGGUGGGAAAGGAUUACCUUUUGUGUGACUACAACAGAGAUGGGGACUCCUAUAGGUCACCAUGGAGUAACAAGUAUGACCCUCCCUUGGAGGAUGGGGCCAUGCCGUCAGCUCGGCUGAGAAAGCUGGAGGUGGAAGCCAACAAUGCCUUUGACCAGUAUCGAGACCUGUAUUUUGAAGGUGGCGUCUCAUCUGUCUACCUCUGGGAUCUGGAUCAUGGCUUUGCUGGAGUGAUCCUCAUAAAGAAGGCUGGAGAUGGAUCAAAGAAGAUCAAAGGCUGCUGGGAUUCCAUCCACGUGGUAGAAGUGCAGGAGAAAUCCAGCGGUCGCACCGCCCAUUACAAGUUGACCUCCACGGUGAUGCUGUGGCUGCAGACCAACAAAUCUGGCUCUGGCACCAUGAACCUCGGAGGCAGCCUUACCAGACAGAUGGAGAAGGAUGAAACUGUGAGUGACUGCUCCCCACACAUAGCCAACAUCGGGCGCCUGGUAGAGGACAUGGAAAAUAAAAUCAGAAGUACGCUGAACGAGAUCUACUUUGGAAAAACAAAGGAUAUCGUCAAUGGGCUGAGAUCUAUUGAUGCUAUCCCUGACAACCAAAAGUUUAAGCAGUUGCAGAGGGAGCUCUCUCAAGUGCUGACCCAGCGCCAGAUCUACAUCCAGCCUGAUAAUUAAGCCGAUCCAGGUCUGUGCAGACUUUUGCAGACAAAUCAAAACAAGAAGCUCUGAAGAAUGACCUGGUGGAGGCUUUGAAGAGAAAGCAGCAAUGCUAAACCUCUGUUUCAUGCUAACCAGACACGCCGUGCACUCGUUAGAUUCCUUUCUUAGAAAACUCGUUUUCUGCUCCCUUCCCUCGUCCCUUCCCUCCCCGACAGGUCACAUAACAGCUGCAUCAUUGACCGCACAGCGCCAUCUCUCCCUGAGAAUAAAGCCGAUAGCCACCCUCCUCCGGCUCCGAGCCUGCUUCUGCCACACCUCGCUCUCAGUUCUCUCCACAUUUCCAUAGAGACCGUGUGGUUUUUGUUCACCCGGGCCCCCCGUCUUCCUCCCUGUCCCCCCAUUUAUAGGCAUAAAAUCCACUGUCUGCCAGCCUCCCUUCCCUCCCACCUUUUUGGUACAUUGGUGUAAAAAAUGUAAAACAAAAAAAUUUUAUGAACUAACUGUGGUGUGUGAAAGAGAGAAGAAAAACUGGAAAUCUUAUUCCGUGUGUGUUUGGGAGUUGCUUGGGGUUGGGGGUCGUGGGGACAGGGGACAGCUCUGGGAGCAGAGGUGGCCCUCGGUGCCGUCCUGCGCAGACUCUCCCGUCCCACGGAGGCCGCGGGGUGGGGGCUGGGGGGGGUGCCGCCGACCGUUCCGCUCUUCCGGCCAGGUGCUUUUCUGUCAAUUUCUAUGGAAUGCAAAAGGAGGUUUUUGUUUUAUUUUGUUUUUUUGUAAAGCUUAAGAAAAAAAUCUACAUCUUAUACUUGAGCCUCCAUACUUAAAAAAAGAAAAGAAAAGAAAUCAAUAAAAAGAAACUGGGGCGCAGUUA